ACACUUUGUAUGGCAAGUGGAACCACUGGCUUGGUGGAUUUUGCUAGAUUUUUCUGAUUUUUAAACUCCUGAAAAAUAUCCCAGAUAACUGUCAUGAAGCUGGUAACUAUCUUCCUGCUGGUGACCAUCAGCCUUUGUAGUUACUCUGCUACUGCCUUCCUCAUCAACAAAGUGCCCCUUCCUGUUGACAAGUUGGCACCUUUACCUCUGGACAACAUUCUUCCCUUUAUGGAUCCAUUAAAGCUUCUUCUGAAAACUCUGGGCAUUUCUGUUGAGCACCUUGUGGAGGGGCUAAGGAAGUGUGUAAAUGAGCUGGGACCAGAGGCUUCUGAAGCUGUGAAGAAACUGCUGGAGGCGCUAUCACACUUGGUGUGACAUCAAGAUAAAGAGCGGAGGUGGAUGGGGAUGGAAGAUGAUGCUCCUAUCCUCCCUGCCUGAAACCUGUUCUACCAAUUAUAGAUCAAAUGCCCUAAAAUGUAGUGACCCGUGAAAAGGACAAAUAAAGCAAUGAAUACA